AGCUUCUAGCUCUCAGUCUGCGCGAGGGUGUAGGAAGGAAAGCCCAGGACCUCCGGAGCAGAGCACAGCAGCUGCAGAGGCAAGGCCAGCAUGUCGCCCAACUUCAAACUUCAGUGUCACUUCAUUCUCAUCUUCCUGACGGCUCUAAGAGGGGAAAGCCGGUACCUAGAGCUGAGGGAAGCGGCGGACUACGAUCCUUUCCUGCUCUUCAGCGCCAACCUGAAGCGGGAGCUGGCUGGGGAGCAGCCGUACCGCCGCGCUCUGCGGUGCCUGGACAUGCUGAGCCUCCAGGGCCAGUUCACCUUCACCGCCGACCGGCCGCAGCUGCACUGCGCAGCCUUCUUCAUCAGCGAGCCCGAGGAGUUCAUUACCAUCCACUACGACCAGGUCUCCAUCGACUGUCAGGGCGGCGACUUCCUGAAGGUAUUUGAUGGUUGGAUUCUCAAGGGGGAGAAGUUCCCCAGUUCCCAGGAUCAUCCUCUCCCCUCAGCUGAGCGGUACAUAGAUUUCUGUGAGAGUGGUCUUAGCAGGAGGAGCAUCAGAUCUUCCCAGAAUGUGGCCAUGAUCUUCUUCCGAGUCCAUGAACCAGGAAAUGGAUUCACAUUAACCAUAAAGACAGACCCCAACCUCUUUCCUUGCAAUGUCAUUUCUCAGACUCCAAAUGGAAAGUUUACCCUGGUAGUUCCACACCAGCAUCGAAACUGCAGCUUCUCCAUAAUUUAUCCUGUGGUGAUCAAAAUAUCUGAUCUUACCCUGGGACACGUAAAUGGUCUUCAGUUAAAGAAAUCCUCAGCAGGUUGCGAGGGAAUAGGAGACUUUGUGGAGCUGCUGGGAGGAACUGGAUUGGACCCUUCCAAGAUGACGCCUUUAGCUGAUCUCUGCUACCCCUUUCAUGGCCCGGCCCAGAUGAAAGUUGGCUGUGACAACACUGUGGUGCGCAUGGUCUCCAGUGGAAAACACGUAAAUCGUGUGACUUUUGAGUAUCGUCAGCUGGAGCCGUACGAGCUGGAAAACCCAAAUGGAAACAGUAUCGGGGAAUUCUGUUUGUCUGGUCUUUGAAUAACCAACCCAGUGAUUUACAUGCUGAUAGCUAAGUGAGUUUUUAAUGGCCAUUGUGUAUGAUUUUGAUGCACAACUAGUUAAAAGCCUUUCAUACCAGUCAGUAUUCCCAGCCUUGAGCGCACGCGCGCACACACACACACACAUACACACACGCAUUAAUUUUUGUACUUUGCUUCUUUUAUGUUUGUAAUCUGUAAAUGAACACAUGGCAGAAAAUAACCCCUGAUUGGUAGGAUCAUAGUUCUAAAUGGAAAUGUUUGUAAUUCUUUGAUGUGCUACAAACCUGAAACUGGUAAGACAAGCACAAAGCAACGUGCAAUACAAAAAUCGUAUCUCAAGGGAAAAUACUCAAAGAAAGAAAAGUGGCAGCACUUAUAUUAGUUUUAUAACAGGAUAAAGUCUUGUGUAUAGCAAAGUAGUUGCAUCUGUUUAUUUUCUAUUUAUUAUUGUUACAAUAGGUAAUAGUUAUAGCAAUUAUUUAUUGAUUUGUAACAACUUGUUUUUAACCAAACUUUGUAGCAUGGAAAAAAUUUUCCAUCCACAAAUACAAACAUGAAUAAAUACAUUCAGAAUGUUGGCACCA